CGCCUCUCGGAGCUGGAAAUGCAGCUAUUGAGAUCUUCGAAUGCUGCGGAGCUGGAGGCGGAGGCAGCUGGGGAGGUCCGAGCGAUGUGACCAGGCCGCCAUCGCUCGUCUCUUCCUCUCUCCUGCCGCCUCCUGUCUCGAAAAUAACUUUUUUAGUCUAAAGAAAGAAAGACAAAAGUAGUCGUCCGCCCCUCACGCCCUCUCUUCCUCUCAGCCUUCCGCCCGGUGAGGAAGCCCGGGGUGGCUGCUCCGCCGUCGGGGCCGCGCCGCCGAGCCCCAGCCGCCCCGGGCCGCCCCCGCACGCCGCCCCCAUGCAUCCCUUCUACACCCGGGCCGCCACCAUGAUAGGCGAGAUCGCCGCCGCCGUGUCCUUCAUCUCCAAGUUUCUCCGCACCAAGGGGCUCACGAGCGAGCGACAGCUGCAGACCUUCAGCCAGAGCCUGCAGGAGCUGCUGGCAGAACAUUAUAAACAUCACUGGUUCCCAGAAAAGCCAUGCAAGGGAUCGGGUUACCGUUGUAUUCGCAUCAACCAUAAAAUGGAUCCUCUGAUUGGACAGGCAGCACAGCGGAUUGGACUGAGCAGUCAGGAGCUGUUCAGGCUUCUCCCAAGUGAACUCACACUCUGGGUUGACCCCUAUGAAGUGUCCUACAGAAUUGGAGAGGAUGGCUCCAUCUGUGUGCUGUAUGAAGCCUCACCAGCAGGAGGUAGCACUCAAAACAGCACCAACGUGCAAAUGGUAGACAGCCGAAUCAGCUGUAAGGAGGAACUUCUCUUGGGCAGAACGAGCCCUUCCAAAAACUACAAUAUGAUGACUGUAUCAGGUUAAGAUAUAGUCUGUGGAUGGAUCAUCUGAUGAUGAUGGAUAAAUUUGAUUUUUGCUUUGGGUGGGCUCCUCUUGGGGAUGGAUUAUGGAAUUUAAACCAUGUCACAGCUGUGAAGAUCUGGCACAAGAUAGAAUGGUAAAAAAAAAAAAAAUUUUAAGUGACAGUGCCAUAGUUUGGACAGUACCUUUCAAUGAUUAAUUUUAAUAGCCUGUGAGUCCAAGUAAAUGAUCACUUUAUUUGCUAGGGAGGGAAGUCCUAGGGUGGUUUCAGUUUCUCCCAGACAUACCUAAAUUUUUACAUCAAUCCUUUUAAAGAAAAUCUGUAUUUCAAAGAAUCUUUCUCUGCAGUAAAUCUCGCAGGGGAAUUUGCACUAUUACACUUGAAAGUUGUUAUUGUUAACCUUUUCGGCAGCUUUUAAUAGGAAAGUUAAACGUUUUAAACAUGGUAGUACUGGAAAUUUUACAAGACUUUUACCUAGCACUUAAAUAUGUAUAAAUGUACAUAAAGACAAACUAGUAAGCAUGACCUGGGGAAAUGGUCAGACCUUGUAUUGUGUUUUUGGCCUUGAAAGUAGCAAGUGACCAGAAUCUGCCAUGGCAACAGGCUUUAAAAAAGACCCUUAAAAAGACACUGUCUCAACUGUGGUGUUAGCACCAGCCAGCUCUCUGUACAUUUGCUAGCUUGUAGUUUUCUAAGACUGAGUAAACUUCUUAUUUUUAGAAAGUGGAGGUCUGGUUUGUAACUUUCCUUGUACUUAAUUGGGUAAAAGUCUUUUCCACAAACCACCAUCUAUUUUGUGAACUUUGUUAGUCAUCUUUUAUUUGGUAAAUUAUGAACUGGUGUAAAUUUGUACAGUUCAUGUAUAUUGAUUGUGGCAAAGUUGUACAGAUUUCUAUAUUUUGGAUGAGAAAUUUUUCUUCUCUCUAUAAUAAAUCGUUUCUUAUCUUGGCAUUUUAAUCAAUCUCUUGUCAUGAUUAUAGAGGUUUAGCUAAAAGUAUUUUUUCUUAGAAGACAGGUUCUAUAAACUGAAUCUCUGUUGCACACUGGUCAUGCUGGAAAAACAUUUGAUGAGGAAUGAAGAUGCUCUGUAUAUACAUGUUUAGGUUUUACAGGAAACACAGGAGUAGCAUGUUUUAAAAAUUUCUAAAGUCAAAACAUGGACACAUUCACAGGCUAAUGAUCUCAUGAAAUAAGGAUAAGAGACCACGGUAGCAUCUACCAAAAAUGUGAUACUCAAAGGAUUACAUUUCAUUGCUUCCCUGUUGAAGUGAAGAUAUAAAUGUUCCAUUCUGACCCACCUUUGAAAAACAAUUACUUUGCCCCAUGGAUUCUUUGUUCAAUUAGAAAUUUCCCCGGGGCAGGUGACCCAUAGUCUUAAAGAACAGGCUAAACACCACAGAGAGAUUGGUUGCUUUUUGCUUUUCAUCACCUGCAAGAUGUACAUAAAAAUCACAUAAGCUGGAAUUCAACAAAAGGUAUGUUUAUGAACUUUUAUUCUCAAAAGUUGAAAUGCUGACUUUCUCGAUUCCUCAUUUUCAGACUUUUAUUUCAGAUAAAUACUAAAAACCUAAGUGAACCUUGAUAAUGCUGUAGUGUAGAUUACUUCACUACCCCAUAUAAUAGAAGGACUUGCUGUUUAGUUGUAGAGGAUAACAGCGUUUUUCAGUGGAAAUUGAAAGUGGAAAAAUUGAAUUUUGCUCUACACAGUUAACAUAUAGUGGCCUUUUUUUGGUAUAUAUGUAAACAUGUUGACACUGGAAAUACGCAGUCUGAAAUAAAAUUAGUAAUUACUUGAAAUUAGUAAUCUCAAAUAACUUUUAAGAAGUUAUUUCUACACCCAGGAAUAAAUUAUUCUGAUUUUGUAGACAACACAGGAAUAGGCCACUGAAUAUGCAGGUAUUUAGAGUACAAAUGUCUGUGGAUAUUAUUGGCACACCAUUCUCGAGAGUUAGAAUUCGUAGACCCGCAACACAUGGACUACCCUUGCCAAUUGUUAUGGUUUUAUUUUUAAACCUAUUCUGUGAAAAAGCUCCUCGGUAUUUCAAACUUGAAUUACAAUAAAAACACCAGGUAGGGUUGUUUUUAAAUGGGUCUCACCCCAGUGCUGACUACUGUUGUUUACCAACUACAUUUCAUCUGGUAACUCCAUUGAAACUAAGUACCUCAACCAUUUUUUUUUUUUAUCAUAAAGCCUUUUUUCAAAUGGAAAGUUGUUUUUGAAGAUCUUGACAUCAGACUUUUUCAAUCUUUGAAAAUGAUGGAAACAGUUAAUAAAAAUGUUUAUUUUAGAAUUCAGGUGAUGUCUGGCUUGUGAGGAGCUGUUUAUAAGUUUGUCUUUGAAAAAGGCUUGCACACAUCACUCUGAGACCAGCUGUUUCCUGUGACUUUAACCUUACCUUCCCCAGACAAUUGAGCUGAACCUGUAUCUGCGGUACAGUAGCUGUUUGUGAUGUAUUUCUUGUUCACUGUUUCUGGGGAAUGUUUUGAAAUAUUUUAUUAUAAAUCCUUUUAAGAUAGGAUGACUACUUUCAAAAUUAUUGUUGCCUUUGGCACCAGGAAUUCAUAGUUGUGAUUGGCAGUAAGUUUGAGGAGUGUUACUUUCUAAGUUUUAACAGGUAGUUUUGAAAUUAUUUCCUUUUUUCCAAAUUUAAGUAGUGCCUCCCUCUGUAAUGUUGAAACAAGGCUUCAAGUGGAUUGUAUAGCAAGAGUUACCCUGGUUCAUGCAGGAUAAUGCGGCUGUUAUCUUUGUCAUCUGGAAUGGGAAUCUCAUGUCUUUAUCCUUAUGUGCAAUAUUUCUAUAAUAAUAGACUGGAAAGGCCACCAGAAAGUGGCUUUCAGGUACAUUGCACAAAUAGUUUCCUUAAGUCAUUAUAACUCACACAUUGCAAGUAAUUAAUUUUGUUUUGUAUAGGUGUUGCAGUUUAUGAAAUUGGCCUUCAAGUUAAAAGGAAGGAAGCCGUAUUCCCGAUGGCUAGUGUUUAAUGACUACAGGUUUCCAGGCUCCCUUUAAUCUUGGGAGCAAAUAAAUCUACUAUUGGACUUCUCCCUGCGUGACUUUUAACAUUUCUGAUACUCUCUCUUCUUCCUCUUUACAGAAGAGAGGUAUGAUAACUGAAGUUGUACUUUGCAUAUUGAAGUUUAAAGAUACUUCCUCUCCCCUUUUCACCCCUAUUUCAAAUGAUGUGAUAAAAUCCUCUUGAUAGGCUAUAUGGAGAACAUUUGUCAAUAGUUUUAUCUAUGCAUGGAAGUCUUCAAAAAGUAUAUCUUGGAUUGUCUAAAACUGAAUAGAUUUCUUAUUUAUCUGAAGGUAUACAGACUGCCAACAUUUUAGACUUAUCUCUCAGUCUCUGCCACUGAACUUUUAUAUAUGGCUGCUAUCAAAAUAUAACCGGUUUAUUUUCAUAUUUGGAACUAAUAUAACAGUAUCACAAAAUCUUUUACAGUAAGAUAGUUUGUAAUACCAGCCGACCCAGCUGCUUAACUGAGUCCUUAAAUCAUUUAAUAUAUGGGACUGUAAAUAGAGAAAUCUGUACAUUAUGAGAUCUGAUUUCUGGUUAUGCCUAUAGAUCUUUAUUUUCUUUAUCCCUAUAGAUCAUUUUCUUCUGAUGUUAAGUGUUAUAUUUUUGAAAUGCUCCUAAACAAGUAAGCCUUAGAUUGUAUUAAUCCUGAGGAUUGAUACCAUUUCCUCAACACUUUGUGGAGUAUGAUUGACACCAGUUUUUUUUUGACUGCAGGUUUAACUUGGCUUAUCACUUUUCGUAUUGCUCAGUAUGUCCAAGAUAGGAAUAAAAAAAUGUAGUUCAA